GCUCUCGAGGUGUCUGGAGGCUCAGCGAGCGCCGGACCCAGGAGGCCCAAGGAGCUGGAGGUGACCCUCAGGCAGCAAGAACCCCACGGAAGGGCGUGAGCCCUGCAGACAGCUGUGCGGCACCUCGGGCUGGGCUCCUGUUAGGAGGAAGUGCCUGCACCCAGGCAGCGGCUCAGAGGCAGCUGCUCCAUGCAGAACUGAAGCUGGUUCUGCAGCAGAAAGGGGAGAGGACACAGGAGCCUGGGGUGCAGGUGCCUCCCAGCAACGCCAUGGAGGCCAGGAGCCGGAGUGCCGAGGAGCUGAGGCGGGCGGAGUUGGUGGAAAUUAUCGUGGAGACGGAGGCGCAGACCGGGGUCAGCGGCAUCAACGUAGCGGGCGGCGGCAAAGAGGGAAUCUUCGUUCGGGAGCUGCGCGAGGACUCACCCGCCGCCAGGAGCCUCAGCCUGCAGGAAGGGGACCAGCUGCUGAGUGCCCGAGUGUUCUUCGAGAACUUCAAGUACGAGGACGCACUACGCCUGCUGCAAUGCGCCGAGCCUUACAAAGUCUCCUUCUGCCUGAAGCGCACUGUGCCCACCGGGGACCUGGCUCUGCGGCCCGGGACCGUGUCUGGCUACGAGAUCAAGGGCCCGCGGGCCAAGGUGGCCAAGCUGGUACGCGUGCUUAGCCCGGCCCCGGCCCUGGACUGCCCCAGCGAUCCGGUCUCUGCGCCGUGAGCCCCAUUCCCCGCCAUCGUGGGCCAGCCUUGCCCUCUGUCUUGUCACUAACCCAAGCUAAUUCCACCCUCUGCCCCUUCCUCUCUGCCCCAAACUCUUCCCCGGGAAGGGGGACAGACCCACCCCAGCCCAGGGCCCUCACCCACCUCGGAGAGGCGUCCCCACCAUCGGAUCCAGGCUUGCUAGGGGUCCUGAACCAGGCUACUUCGAACCAGGAAAGCCAGAUUCCAGCCUGAGUGCUGGCCCAAUUACUGCUGAGUGGCCCUGGACAAAGUUGUUUCUCUCCCUGGGCCUCAGUUUCCCCAUCUCUAGAAUGAGGAUGUUGGGGAAAAUCCCGGAUCAGGAUCUAGAAGUCUUGGGUCCCCGUCCCUACACUCCUGUUGACUCAUUUGGAGAUCCUAGAUGGCUGCCUGCUUUCCUGGGCACUCAUGGUGAAAUGACAGGCAAGAAGUGGGGAUGAUGUUUGGGGAACAAGAUACUUGACCCAGCACAUCCCCCGCCUGGUCCAAUACCAGGUGGGGCUCUUCCUGUCCACUCCCAGCCUCCCACUGUCCCACCGCCUCCUGCCUCUCUCCUCUCUCCCCAGAACAUCCAGAGUCUGUCCCCUGUGAAGAAGAAGAAGAUGGUGCCUGGGGCUCUGGGGGUCCCCGCUGACCUGGCCCCUGUUGACGUCGAGUUCUCCUUUCCCAAGUUCUCCCGCCUGCGUCGGGGCCUCAAAGCCGAGGCUGUCAAGGGUCCUGUCCCGGCUGCCCCUGCCCGCCGGCGCCUCCAGCUGCCUCGGCUGCGUGUACGAGAAGUGGCCGAAGAGGCUCAGGCAGCCCGGCUGGCCGCCGCCGCUCCUCCCCCCAGGAAAGCCAAGGUGGAGGCUGAGGUGGCUGCAGGAGCUCGUUUCACAGCCCCUCAGGUGGAGCUGGUUGGGCCGCGGCUGCCAGGGGCGGAGGUGGGUGUCCCCCAGGUCUCAGCCCCCAAGGCUGCCCCCUCAGCAGAGGCAGCUGGUGGCUUUGCCCUCCACCUGCCAACCCUUGGGCUCGGAGCCCCGGCUCCGCCUGCUGUGGAGGCCCCAGCCGUGGGAAUCCAGGUCCCCCAGGUGGAGCUGCCUGCCUUGCCCUCACUGCCCACUCUGCCCACACUUCCCUGCCUAGAGACCCGGGAAGGGGCUGUGUCGGUAGUGGUGCCCACCCUGGAUGUGGCAGCACCGACUGUGGGGGUGGACCUGGCCUUGCCGGGUGCAGAGGUGGAGGCCCGGGGAGAGGCACCUGAGGUGGCCCUGAAGAUGCCCCGCCUUAGUUUUCCCCGAUUUGGGGCUCGAGCAAAGGAAGUUGCUGAGGCCAAGGUAGCCAAGGUCAGCCCUGAGGCCAGGGUGAAAGGUCCCAGACUUCGAAUGCCCACCUUUGGGCUUUCCCUCUUGGAGCCCCGGCCCGCUGCUCCUGAAGUUGUAGAGAGCAAGCUGAAGCUGCCCACCAUCAAGAUGCCCUCCCUUGGCAUCGGAGUGUCAGGGCCCGAGGUCAAGGUGCCCAAGGGACCUGAAGUGAAGCUCCCCAAGGCUCCUGAGGUCAAGCUUCCAAAAGUGCCCGAGGCAGCCCUUCCAGAGGUUCGACUCCCAGAGGUGGAGCUCCCCAAGGUGUCAGAGAUGAAACUCCCAAAGGUGCCAGAGAUGGCUGUGCCGGAGGUGCGGCUUCCAGAGGUAGAGCUGCCCAAAGUGUCAGAGAUGAAACUCCCAAAGGUGCCAGAGAUGGCUGUGCCGGAGGUGCGGCUUCCAGAGGUACAGCUGCUGAAAGUGUCGGAGAUGAAACUCCCAAAGGUGCCAGAGAUGGCUGUGCCGGAGGUGCGGCUUCCAGAGGUACAGCUGCCGAAAGUGUCAGAGAUGAAACUCCCAGAGGUGUCAGAGGUGGCUGUGCCAGAGGUGCGGCUUCCAGAGGUGCAGCUGCCGAAAGUGCCAGAGAUGAAAGUCCCUGAGAUGAAGCUUCCAAAGGUGCCUGAGAUGAAACUUCCUGAGAUGAAACUCCCUGAAGUGCAACUCCCGAAGGUGCCCGAGAUGGCCGUGCCCGAUGUGCACCUCCCAGAAGUGCAGCUUCCAAAAGUCCCAGAGAUGAAGCUCCCUGAGAUGAAACUCCCUGAGGUGAAACUCCCGAAGGUGCCCGAGAUGGCUGUGCCCGAUGUGCACCUCCCGGAAGUGCAGCUCCCGAAAGUCCCAGAGAUGAAACUCCCUAAAAUGCCUGAGAUGGCUGUGCCAGAGGUUCGACUCCCCGAGGUGCAGCUGCCAAAAGUCUCAGAGAUGAAACUCCCCAAGGUGCCUGAAAUGGCCGUGCCCGAUGUGCACCUCCCAGAGGUGCAGCUGCCCAAAGUCUGUGAAAUGAAAGUCCCUGACAUGAAGCUCCCAGAGAUAAAACUCCCCAAGGUGCCUGAGAUGGCUGUGCCCGAUGUGCACCUCCCCGAGGUGCAGCUGCCGAAAGUGUCAGAGAUUCGGCUGCCGGAAAUGCAAGUGCCGAAGGUUCCCGACGUGCAUCUUCCGAAGGCACCAGAGGUGAAGCUGCCCAGGGCUCCGGAGGUGCAGCUAAAGGCCACCAAGGCAGAACAGGCAGAAGGGAUGGAAUUUGGCUUCAAGAUGCCCAAGAUGACCAUGCCCAAGCUAGGGAGGGCAGAGUCCCCAUCACGUGGCAAGCCAGGCGAGGCGGGUGCUGAGGUCUCAGGGAAGCUGGUAACACUUCCCUGUCUGCAGCCAGAGGUGGAUGGUGAGGCUCAUGUGGGUGUCCCCUCUCUCACUCUGCCUUCAGUGGAGCUAGACCUGCCAGGAGCACUUGGCCUGCAGGGGCAGGUCCCAGCCGCUAAAAUGGGCAAGGGAGAGCGGGUGGAGGGCCCUGAGGUGGCAGCAGGGGUCAGGGAAGUGGGCUUCCGAGUGCCCUCUGUUGAAAUUGUCACCCCACAGCUGCCCGCCGUGGAAAUUGAGGAAGGGCGGCUGGAGAUGAUAGAGACAAAAGUCAAGCCCUCUUCCAAGUUCUCCUUACCUAAGUUUGGACUCUCGGGGCCAAAGGUGGCUAAGGCAGAGGCUGAGGGGGCUGGGCGAGCUACCAAGCUGAAGGUAUCCAAAUUUGCCAUCUCACUCCCCAAGGCUCGGGUGGGGGCUGAGGCUGAGGCCAAAGGGGCUGGGGAGGCAGGCCUGCUGCCUGCCCUCGAUCUGUCCAUCCCACAGCUCAGCCUGGAUGCCCACCUGCCCUCAGGCAAGGUAGAGGUGGCAGGGGCCGACCUCAAGUUCAAGGGGCCCAGGUUUGCUCUCCCCAAGUUUGGGGUCAGAGGCCGGGACACUGAGGCAGCAGAACUAGUGCCAGGGGUGGCUGAGUUGGAGGGCAAGGGCUGGGGCUGGGAUGGGAGGGUGAAGAUGCCCAAGCUGAAGAUGCCUUCCUUUGGGCUGGCUCGAGGGAAGGAAGCAGAAGUUCAAGGUGAUCGUGCCAGCCCGGGGGAAAAGGCUGAGUCCACCGCUGUGCAGCUUAAGAUCCCCGAGGUGGAGCUGGUCACGCUGGGCGCCCAGGAGGAAGGGAGGGCAGAGGGGGCUGUGGCCGUCAGUGGAAUGCAGCUGUCAGGCCUGAAGGUGUCCACAGCCGGGCAGGUGGUCACUGAGGGCCAUGACGCGGGGCUGAGGAUGCCUCCGCUGGGCAUCUCCCUGCCACAGGUGGAGCUGACCGGCUUUGGGGAGGCAGGUACCCCAGGGCAGCAGGCUCAGAGUACAGUCCCUUCAGCAGAGGGCACAGCAGGCUACAGGGUUCAGGUGCCCCAGGUGACCCUGUCUCUGCCUGGAGCCCAGGUUGCAGGUGGUGAGCUGCUGGUGGGUGAGGGUGUCUUUAAGAUGCCCACCGUGACAGUGCCCCAGCUUGAGCUGGACGUGGGGCUAAGCCGAGAGGCACAGGCGGGCGAGGCGGCCACAGGCGAGGGUGGGCUGAGGCUGAAGUUGCCCACACUGGGGGCCAGAGCUAGGGUGGGGGGCGAGGGUGCUGAGGAGCAGCCCCCAGGGGCCGAGCGUACCUUCUGCCUCUCACUGCCCGACGUGGAGCUCUCGCCAUCCGGGGGCAACCAUGCCGAGUACCAGGUGGCAGAGGGGGAGGGAGAGGCCGGACACAAGCUCAAGGUACGGCUGCCCCGGUUUGGCCUGGUGCGGGCCAAGGAGGGGGCCGAGGAGGGUGAGAAGGCCAAGAGCCCCAAACUCAGGCUGCCCCGAGUGGGCUUCAGCCAAAGUGAGAUGGUCACUGGGGAAGGGUCCCCCAGCCCCGAGGAGGAGGAGGAGGAGGAGGAAGAGGGCAGUGGGGAAGGGGCCUCGGGUCGCCGGGGCCGGGUCCGGGUCCGCUUGCCACGUGUAGGCCUGGCGGCCCCUUCUAAAGCCUCUCGGGGGCAGGAGGGCGAUGCAGCCCCCAAGUCCCCCGUCAGAGAGAAGUCACCCAAGUUCCGCUUCCCCAGGGUGUCCCUAAGCCCCAAGGCCCGGAGUGGGAGUGGGGACCAGGAAGAGGGUGGAUUGCGGGUGCGGCUGCCCAGCGUGGGGUUUUCAGAGACAGGGGCUCCAGGCCCGGCCAGGAUGGAGGGGGCUCAGGCUGCGGCUGUCUGAAGCCCCUAGUCAGAUGGGGAUCCCUUCUUGCCUUCCUUUCUCUACCCCCUCGCUGUUGUGUGUGUGAUAACUAGCACUAACCCUAAGAGGGCCGGGAGGUGGGUGACUGACCAGGGCUGGCAGGGAGGCCUGCUCCUGUCUCUCUGGCAGGAGUGCCUGUACCCCACCAAGCCAUGUGAAUAAAAUAAUCUGGAAGUAGCCA